ACAUGGCCUGUGGAGGAAACACCUGAGCAGUGUUUCCUCCACAGGGGUCUCAGUCUGGGCUCUAAAGAGCUCCUCCACCAAGUUUCUAAAUUUUAAUAAUUUCAGCCUAUUGUUCCCCCAGAGUAGUAACUGCUUUCUGGAACUGAACUCUGUGAUAAUGUAGUAUUUACUUUUUGCCUUUUCAAUAACCUAGUUAACAAUUUUAUACCUACUGAGUUCUAUUUAAAUAAUGGUAUUUUCUAUCUCCUGACUGGACAGAUACCCAGGAGUAGGGUUUGAACUUCCUACUUUCUGGUUUGCAUAUAUCUUAUUAAGAUAACUAAAGUACUUGCUACUUGCCAGUCUUCAGACCCGGUCAGUGUAAUGUCAUCAGUGCAGCAGAUCAGUGUGAUGUGUGAUUUCUCAAUGUGAUCAAAAUCUCUGGACUAUUUUAGAGAGCAAGAGUGUUAACAUAGACCUGAAGCAAGACUGUAAUGGUUGAACAAAGCACAAAGUGCUUCUGAGAUUUUUUGCAAAUUAAUAGGAAGAAAAAAGCAUUUGCUUCCAAGUUAUAAGAAUUGUGUUGAUUUGACCCCGUAAAAAUACUACAUCUUGAAUACUAGCUGCAAUUACAGUCACGACCUUUCUGUGUUUAUAAUUCAUAGCUAUUCUCCAAGAUCCAUCUGUCUUAUAUUUAGAUCAAACAGGAGCAGCUGCAUUGGCAUGGAAGAAUCCUAUUUCAAGCUGGUUUACUGCUAUGCUCCACUGUUUUGGUGGAGGAAUUUUAUCCUGUCUACUGCUUGCAGAGCCUCCAUUGAAGUUUCUUGCAAACCACACUAACAUAUUACUGGCAUCUUCAAUCUGGUAUAUUACAUUUUUUUGCCCGCAUGACCUAGUUUCCCAGGGCUAUUCAUAUCUACCUGUUCAACUACUGGCUUCGGGAAUGAAGGAAGUGACCAGAACUUGGAAAAUAGUAGGUGGAGUCACACAUGCUAAUAGCUAUUACAAAAAUGGCUGGAUAGUCAUGAUAGCUAUUGGAUGGGCCCGAGGUGCAGGUGGUACCAUUAUAACGAAUUUUGAGAGGUUGGUAAAAGGAGAUUGGAAACCAGAAGGUGAUGAAUGGCUGAAGAUGUCAUACCCUGCCAAGGUAACCCUGCUGGGGUCAGUUAUCUUCACAUUCCAGCACACCCAGCAUCUGGCAAUAUCAAAGCAUAAUCUUAUGUUCCUUUAUACCAUCUUUAUUGUGGCCACAAAGAUAACCAUGAUGACUACACAGACUUCUACUAUGACAUUUGCUCCUUUUGAGGAUACAUUGAGUUGGAUGCUAUUUGGCUGGCAGCAGCCGUUUUCAUCAUGUGAGAAGAAAAGUGAAGCAAAGUCACCUUCCAAUGGCGUUGGGUCAUUGGCCUCAAAGCCGGUAGAUGUUGCCUCAGAUAAUGUUAAAAAGAAACAUACUAAGAAGAAUGAAUAAAUUUACGUGAUGAGCUCUACAAGGCCAAAAAUUUUUUUUCUUAUCUACCUGUUAUAUUGUGCUAAUUUUUCUAUGUAUGUGAUGUGAAAUGAAGACUAUAUAUAUGGAAUGGAGGUGACAGAAAGAAAGAAAUUCUUUGUUUGAGGGAGACUUCCCCUUUCUGGAUUGUAUUUGUAGAGUGUUACGAGUGUAUCAUGUGAUUAUGCUUUACCGGUAUAAGAGAUUCUGUUGUGAUUAUUUGAAUAGUUUUAUAUUAAUAAAAGAAGACAAAAUUUUUUAAAUGUUAGAAAAAGCAGAUCUGUCAUUGCAAAGUAACAAAAAUUUUAAGCUUUUAAAAAUGUAGAUUUUUCAUAUUUUUAAAAUUUGAAUCUAUUUGAGCUUUAGUUCAGCAGAAUUAAAUUUUUACUUGACAUUAUCAUUAAAAUUGCUAGGUAUGGAGAACAAUUCCUAUUUUAUUUUGAACACUGAGAAGAGUAAACUUUUCCUAAAACACUUUAUAUUAUAAAUGAAAAUAAAUUGCUAGUUUAUAUUUUAGAUAUAAACAUCAUAUUUUUUAUUAAUACCUACAUCAAAUGGAAAAUAUCUGAAAUUUUUUUUCCAUAGCAGGUAUUUUCUACUAGAAGUAGUUUUACUACUUUUCAUUUAGAACAGAGUAUGAGUCUUAAUCUGAAGUCUUUUUCAUGCCCUUGUUUUAAAAAAACUACUUUUUUUGGCCUCAAAAAAAUCAAGGGUGUAAUUUUUAAUAAAUUGUUAAUCCUAUGUUUUGUAAUUUUCAUUUUAGGAGCUUGACUUAUUUUUUUCUCUCUCAUAAAAACACAUUUGUUUUAAUUGUAGGAGAAAUUUUCUCAGCAUUUUGCAUGUUCUUUCUAAUCUUUGUUGGUCUGAAUAUAUUGGUAGUAAUUACUGUAAUUAUUCAACAAAAAGCAUAUCCGUUCAAAAAUUUUUCCACUAUGUCUUUUUUCUAGUGGCUACUGUUUUAGUUUUCUAGUUGAAUAUCUCUGACAAGCUUUCGUAUGGUUUUGUUAUAUUUUCAUCUACAUGUAAUGUGUUAUUAAUUUUAUUAAAUGAAAACUAAUCACCUUCAUGUGGAAAUGCUCUGAGAAUUGUCCUUAGGCAUUUGGUAGUAACCAGCUAACCAAGAAGAAACAGAGAAACCAGAACUUCAUAUGGCAGUCCAUUUAGAUGAAGAAUGAUGAUAUAAAAUCUGGUUCCUUCUUAGCAAAAUAAAAAACAAACAAGAAAAGAUACUAAAUGAUGUUAAUUUUCUUACUUUAUGAUUUAGAAGUCCAGUUAUAAUAUUAAAACUCUGUGACAUAGUUUCUUUUACCAAAACCAUGAACCUACUCCCCGUAUCAGGUAUUUUCGAUGGUUUAGAAGUACUCAAGUCACAUCACAUUCAAGUUAGAAGUUUUUUUUUUGUUGUUGUUAUUUUAAAUUUUUAACAAAUAUAAACACCAGCAGAUACUAUUACUUGCUUAAAAAAUUGGGAGGGGGCACUUUUCAUAGUCUUGGAAUGCUAAGAAGUUUUAUUUUUAAUAUUGUGACAGAAAGCUUUAAGUAUUUAAGAGCUCUGUAUUAUAUUUGAUACUCUUACAGUUAAAAACUUUUCAAAAUUAAUACAUUGUUAAUUAUUGACCAGUUUUGAAGUUUGGGUUUAACUGUAGUUGAAAUGGAAGGACUCUUGUUUUACACUUGUAUUAAAGAUAAAUUUAUUAAAAUAAGUUAUUUAGCACCAAUGGAGUAUUACAUUAUUUUUAUGUUUUAUAUUUUUCUUGAGGUAGAGUUUCAGAACUCAUCUAGUAUUUUGACUAAUAUAGUAUAUAUUCAGUGAUUACUGUUCAAAUGGGACAUUGGUAGAAACUUUAUUAAUCUAUGCAAGUAUCCUAUAACCCUCAAUUCAAGGCUCUUUUGUAAAAAAUGUACUGGAGAACAUGGCUUAGGCCUGAAACCCAUCCUGAAUCUAUUCAGGUCACCUGUAGAGUCUUGACUUGGAUUUGCAAAGCAGAUUGUUAGACUCCUUACCCAAUGUGAAGUGUGAAUAAGGCCUAUAGGCCUGCCUCACACAGCUAAUCAGAGGUGGCACUGAGAAAGUCAAGUCCUAAUAGGUCUCCUUAAAAAAAAAAAGGAGACAAAAAGCUGGCAAGAACAUGAGCCAGCUUCCCUCAGUGCUGUCACUCUCAAGUAAAACAUGGCCAAAUGAAUAUCAAACUGGUUUAUCAGAUUAGUCACUCUUCCUUACUGAGGGAGUAUCAAGUAAGGGCUGGAGAGAGACCAGAUAUGUGGAGUUGUUGGCUUUCAGUGGAAAUGGUAGCCUCCCUGUGGGUAGAGACCAAAAGGUAGAGAGAUGACAGAAGGGAGACUCUGAUUAGUGUAUUUUUUUUUUGUCUAUUCCUUAAAGCCCAGACACCUUUCCAUUAAAAUCUACUUCAAAUCACAAGUUGAUUACAAUUGAGUGGAACAUCCCAUGUUGUAAAUGGAAUAAUGUGUUCAGAAUGCUCUUUCUUUCCCCCAAUAAAGCCCUUUAUAGUGUUUGCCCCAGGUGUAAUUCA